AGUCCAAGAAGAGAACCUACAAACUAGACUUGUAGAUUAAAAUUAUCUGAUCAAAAAGGCAGACUCUGUAAAUUUCCUUAAGACCUACCUUGGCAUAAAGGCUGACCCAGCAAAAGAACUGAGACAGGGUCUCGCUAUGUUGGCCAGAUCGGUCUUGAAUUCCCGACCUCAAGCAAUCCUCCCGACUCAACGUCCCAAAGUGCUAGUGUUACAGGCAUGAGUCACCAUGCCUGGUUCCUCACUUUCGUUAUCUGUAAAAUGGGACUAAUAGUGAUACUUAUUACUGUGAAACUUAAGACACCUUUUUUUUUUUUUUUUUUUUUUUAAAUAGAGACAAAGUCUCACUACGUUGCCUAGGCUGGUCUCUAACUCCUGGACUCAAGCAAUCCUCCUGUCUCGGCCUCCCGAAGUGCUGGGAGCCAGACACGUUUUUAAUAACAAUAAAGCAACUAAUACUUUACUGAGAGCUUACUCUGUGCCACUGGCUUCACAUCAGUUUGUACAUAUGAAGUAUUUGGUAUGAUUCCUGGCACAUGCUAAACAAUAUAUAUAUUAGCUAAUAUUAUUAAUCAUUACUAUCUAAAGAAUCAUGAACAAAGUUAACAAUGGUUUAAUACAGAUACUUGAGACAGUUUCAGGGGCAAGAAAGGCAUCUACUAAAGGUGCUAGAAAUUUGGCUAUCAAAGACCUUCUUGAGAAUGCAAUAUCAAUCAUUUUUGGAAAGACUGUUAUUUCACCAAACGCUUCCUGUAUUAAAAAAAAAAAUUAACUGGCUUUGAAGUUAGCUAGACUUGAAUAACCAUCCAAAUAAUCCAAAGCUCCUAUUUGCCUUGUGUAAAUUUCUUUUAUCUGUCUGAGCACCAGUGACUUCAUCUGAAAAUGGGAACAAUGGCUAUCUUGUUGAGAUACUGAAGAAUUAAGAGAUAAUACAGUAUGAAAGCAGUUAUCACAGUGCCUAUGAAGAUUUUGUUGUUUCCAAAGCGUAGAGAUCAGGUCUCCUAAAACAUUUAAAAAUAAUCUAACAAAAUAAGGGUCAUUAAGUAGCUAUGCCAAGAAAAAAGAAUACACUAAAUGAUUAUGACAACUUGUUAGGGUAAUAAGUUAUAAAACAUUAAAAUAAUGCACUAAGAUUUUUUAAAGUCUAUAUCAUAUGAAACUGAAAUCGCCAUCUAACCUAAAUAAACUGAACAAUCAUCCCAGUGUUCCAUUAGCUCAAAUCUGAAGAAAAUACAAAAAAAAGUCUCUAAUCACCAAUAAAUGUUAAGUUACCUCAGAGCAAAAGAAAGUUGUAUAUACCCAGGUGGCCAAUAUCCAAUUCCAACAACACAGAAAGGCAGUCUCCAAAGCCUCAAAGUCCCGAGAUAUAGGAACUAGGAAACCCAAGCAACAACCUAGCUCCACAAGUCUGUAGUGCCCUUCUCAAGCCCCAUUAAAAGGCAGGAAGUGGGUAUGCAGCACUCUCAAGGGUAUCUACCUCUAAAGGAAGAAGCAAAGAGGACAGUCAAAUAUAAACUCAUAGUCCUGAAUUGUAGCAAACAAGAGAGGCUCACUCAAGGGAAGCAAAGCUGCAUUUCCUGUUCUGUUCCUAGUAACUGCUACACUAAAGUCUUAAGACACCUUUGUCAUACGCAAGGAUGAUUACAAGGAAGGCACACAUUAGAUUUCUACUCACCACCUUGAGAAAAGGAUAACCACUGAUGAAAACUGUUUGCAGCAGAAAACUAAUUAUACUAAUGUUAUCUUUUUAAAAUUCUUAUUUAACCCCUUAAUGAUUAUUUUAGUUCAUUGAACUAUUCAACCUUUUUCUUCUAGUUUACUUACUUUUAAAGCUAAUGCUAUCCAGAAAUGUCUUCCUGGAAUUUCUUAUUUUGCCAAGAAACAAUUCUCUUUCUACCCCCCAAUCUAAUCAGAGCCUAGAAUAUGCAAAGAGAUAGCAAUCCAUCAUCCAGGACAGAAAGAAUCCACGAACAUGGUUGCAAAGUGACAAAAACAAAUAAAGCCUAAUCAUAAAACUCUAAAUAAGACCAGGUAUGGUGGCUCACCCCUGUAAUCCCAGCGCUUUGGAAGGCUGAAGUGGGAAGAUGGCUUGAGAACAGGAGUCUGAGACCAGCCUAGGCAAUAUAUUGAGCCCAGUACCAACAAAAAUUAAAAUUCUAAAAAUUUGCUGAGGUUGCAGUGAGCUAUGAUUGUGCCACUGCACUCCAGCCUAGGAGACAGAGCAAGACCCUGUCUCUAAAAAUACAAAUCAAUAAAUCAAACUCUGAAUAGGCUAAUUAUAAAGCAUACAUUAGAACUACAAACCUCUAAAAGCUUACCACAAAUGUAAGCCUUGUCCUAUACUAAAUCUGGCUUCAAAGGAUUUGCAGACAGUUUAAUAAUAAGCUUCCAAAUGACUUCUAAUUAUUUACACAGAAGAACACUUACAUAUUUAAACAUACCCCUUUUAAUUAUGAAUAAUGCAUAAUUAUAAAUUAACUAUGAAAUGCUAGUCUUUAUACACAAUAUUUGGUCAAAUCAAUAAAUGCUUGACACCCGGACUUGUGCAAGGAAGACACAGGGGUAUAUAAUCUCUACCUACAGGAAUUCUAAAAUAUACUUAGAAAAUGUUUAAGUGUUAAACAAUGUUUUAACUGUCAUUCAAAGAAACAAUAGAAGAGAUAUUUUAAGGUAACACACAAUUAGCUCCCAAAUGAAUGACUUAGUAAAUGCCAUCUAACGUGAAGAGAAAAGCGAGAGAGUUGGCAAAGUUGUGGUUAGAGAAGCAUUCCCAAGAAAGCAGAAAGUCCAUGAGCUCUCCAAAUUCACAAACAUUAACUAUAAAACAGUUAAGAGCUUACUAAUUUACUCUUGAUUUUAGAGAAAUACAGCCUGAGAUGGACAGCAGUAAUUGCAAAGUUAUUGCUCCUCUCCUAAGUCAAAGAUACCGGAGGAUGGUCACCAAGGAUGGCCACAGCACACUUCAAAUGGAUGGCGCUCAAAGAGGUCUUGCAUAUCUUCGAGAUGCUUGGGGAAUCCUAAUGGACAUGCGCUGGCGUUGGAUGAUGUUGGUCUUUUCUGCUUCUUUUGUUGUCCACUGGCUUGUCUUUGCAGUGCUCUGGUAUGUUCUGGCUGAGAUGAAUGGUGAUCUGGAACUAGAUCAUGAUGCCCCACCUGAAAACCACACUAUCUGUGUCAAGUAUAUCACCAGUUUCACAGCUGCAUUCUCCUUCUCCCUGGAGACACAACUCACAAUUGGUUAUGGUACCAUGUUCCCCAGUGGUGACUGUCCAAGUGCAAUCGCCUUACUUGCCAUACAAAUGCUCCUAGGCCUCAUGCUAGAGGCUUUUAUCACAGGUGCUUUUGUGGCGAAGAUUGCCCGGCCAAAAAAUCGAGCUUUUUCAAUUCGCUUUACUGACACAGCAGUAGUAGCUCACAUGGAUGGCAAACCUAAUCUUAUCUUCCAAGUGGCCAACACCCGACCUAGCCCUCUAACCAGUGUCCGGGUCUCAGCUGUACUCUAUCAGGAAAGAGAAAAUGGCAAACUCUACCAGACCAGUGUGGAUUUCCACCUUGAUGGCAUCAGUUCUGACGAAUGUCCAUUCUUCAUCUUUCCACUAACGUACUAUCACUCCAUUACACCAUCAAGUCCUCUGGCUACUCUGCUCCAGCAUGAAAAUCCUUCUCACUUUGAAUUAGUUGUAUUCCUUUCAGCAAUGCAGGAGGGCACUGGAGAAAUAUGCCAAAGGAGGACAUCCUACCUACCGUCUGAAAUCAUGUUACAUCACUGUUUUGCAUCUCUGUUGACCCGAGGUUCCAAAGGUGAAUAUCAAAUCAAGAUGGAGAAUUUUGACAAGACUGUCCCUGAAUUUCCAACUCCUCUGGUUUCUAAAAGCCCAAACAGGACUGACCUGGAUAUCCACAUCAAUGGACAAAGCAUUGACAAUUUUCAGAUCUCUGAAACAGGACUGACAGAAUAAGACUUAUCCAUUUUUUAAUGUAUUAAAUACACCCAGCCAGUUAUGCAGCUACUUUUUCUUUACUGUAUCUCAUGUUUUCUUUUUUCAAUGCUAAUUAUAGCUCUCUACAUCACGGUAAUCAUGCCUAUGCCUACAUAAGAAUGGCUGAGCUAACAAUACACAUUCUGGAAACAUAACACUCUACAUUACAAAGUUUGUUACCUGCUGAAAUCAAUGUAACUCAACUUGACAGACACUUAUACAGAAAUGUUGCUGGUGAAUUUAUAAGAAUGUGGUAUGAUACUAGUAAUGAAGGCAAAAUGGACAGUGAAGUUUAACACAACUGAACUCUAAGAAAAUCAACCAUUAAUCUCUCAUUUUCAUCUGCAAAUUGAAGCAACAGUUUAGUUUCAAACCUAGCUCCCUGGGUGGAAUGACGACUUCACUAUACUUAGUGAAUAUCCUUUAAGAGCUGGGAUUUUUUUCAAGACAACAAAGAUCAUUCAUUUGGUUCUUUAUACUAUGAAACUUGAGUAAGUAUUACCUCCUUAAUUUUUAACAACUAAGAACAAAAAUUAACGAGAAAAACAACAAAGUACAGAUUUAUACAUAAACCUAAAAGCAUUUGAACAUGACACCCGAACACAUACAUAUAUGUUCACUUAUUUGUGGCAGAAGGUGAUCAGAUAAGCUCCAGCCCAAAUGGAACCUGUGGGGUGGUAUUUUGCAUUGCAAGGAGACGCAAAAUUUUAUUUUAAAACUGUCCUCCAUAAUAAUCAAACGGUGAUUCAUCUAAAUGACUUCUAGCAACCUAAGUAAAAACAUUCCCCUCCUAUGUAUGAUUCAUUUGAUCAUAUAAAACAUCAUGAUGGCUCUAAUUCAUAAAUACAAAAAUAUAUUUAAGUCUUUAUAGAUAUAAAGCUUUACUUAGAUAUAACUUGAGUGAGUAGGGAAAAAAAUCUACAGUAGAUAAAGCAAAAGAUAAUUAGGCAACAAAGCAUUUUCAAACUCAAAUUCCUGUUUCCAACUUCAAAUAGUUUUUUCUAUAAACACAAAAUCAGUGUUUAUUCACCAGUAGGAGGUUGGACUAGAUGAACUCUAUUAUUUCUUUCUAAAUCUAAUAGUCUAUAAAAAUUAUGUUUCCUCUGUUUUUUAUUUUAUCUAUGCUAAAAUGAGCCCUUUCCCUUAUGUCCAGUUUAAGAUGAUCAUUUGCAUGAUUUUCAUUUCAAUAAAAAAAAGAGAAACUGUCCUUAAAACAAAACAAAAACCAAAAAAGUCACCCUAUCAGGUUUCAAACAGAUUUGUGGCUGUUCUUUUCUGAAAUUUCCCUUAUUCAGGUUUCUGUGGGAAAAAUGAAAGAUUAACCUUCCCCACUGGUGAUGACCUAGGCAGGAAUCAUCUCUUGAAAUAAAUACUAGCUGAGUAAAGGCAAGCAGGUGUGAAGAGCAGGGCUCAGCAGCAAGUCACAUUUUUCUACUAUUUGACCAAAAGGAAAAGAAAAUAAAGAAGAACUCUGGAGUGGUCUAAGACUGAUAAUAGCAGAAGAAUAUCAAGAACACAGAAACUUAAUUAUUGUGAACUUUUGCUGUUUGAAAAUCUUAGACAUUCAUUCUUAAGUAGAAAUCAGACCAACAGAUUUUCCCAACCCAAGACUAUUGUAACACAUAAAGACAGCAAGAAUUCUUAUUUCUAUAAUAAAUUAACAAGAUUCACCUAACCUUUGAAAAUAAAGUAGUAUUGAAGACUUACAUGGUAUGUUUUUUCCUAAAGGCACUACAUCACUUACACAGUUCACCCUCUCGCUUGUUAAGUGAAGCUGCCCAAGGUGACAUAAGUGAAUGAGUAAAACCUGAGAUCUAAGGUUCCAUUUAAGUCAGAUGAGUUUCAUAUUAUACUUACUGUUUAUAAUAAAUUUGGCAUUUGAAAACUAAAUAUGACUUCCCCUACACAUGCCAAAAAAAACUAUUGGUAAACUACUGUUAUUUAAUAAACACUUUAUAAAUCUAUAAGAAACGUGAUCCAAAACUUUUUUGCAGGAGAUAGAAAGUUUCUGGGAGGACUGUUCAUUGUUUCUUUCACUUAUUUCAAAUCACAGUUUCUAGGUUAAGGAUUAGGUUUUCUAUAGAAAGACCAUUAUCCUCUGAGGAAAAGGAAGUAACAAUGGAAAAAGGGCGGAAAUUACUGGGAGGGAGGAAUGGCUGCUCUGCCUUUCUGGAUGUGCAGCUCACUAACCUGGAUCAUCUGGGAGCUUGGUCAUGAAGUCUUGCACACAUGAUCAGGAAGACUACUUCGGAACUAACUUUAAACGUUCCUUUGGAAACUGAUAAAGAUAGCAUGACAGUUUCAACAAACUGGAGGCAUGUCGUUACCUAAAAAUCUCAGGGGCCUAGUUUUACAUAUGUACAAGCCC